CUCAAAAUGGAGGUAAAACCGCCGCCCGGUCGCCCCCAGCCCGACUCCGGCCGUCGCCGUCGCCGCCGGGGGGAGGAGGGCCAUGAUCCAAAGGAACCAGAGCAGUUGAGAAAACUGUUUAUUGGUGGUCUGAGCUUUGAAACUACAGAUGAUAGUUUACGAGAACAUUUUGAGAAAUGGGGCACACUCACAGAUUGUGUGGUAAUGAGAGACCCCCAAACAAAACGUUCCAGGGGCUUUGGUUUUGUGACUUAUUCUUGUGUUGAAGAGGUGGAUGCAGCAAUGUGUGCUCGACCACACAAGGUUGAUGGGCGUGUAGUGGAACCAAAGAGAGCUGUUUCUAGAGAGGAUUCUGUAAAGCCUGGUGCCCAUCUAACAGUGAAGAAAAUUUUUGUUGGUGGUAUUAAAGAAGAUACAGAAGAAUAUAAUUUGAGAGACUACUUUGAAAAGUAUGGCAAGAUUGAAACCAUAGAAGUUAUGGAAGACAGGCAGAGUGGAAAAAAGAGAGGAUUUGCUUUUGUAACUUUUGAUGAUCAUGAUACAGUUGAUAAAAUUGUUGUUCAGAAAUACCACACUAUUAAUGGGCAUAAUUGUGAAGUGAAAAAGGCCCUUUCUAAACAAGAGAUGCAGUCUGCUGGAUCACAGAGAGGUCGUGGAGGUGGAUCUGGCAAUUUUAUGGGUCGCGGAGGGAACUUUGGAGGUGGUGGAGGUAAUUUUGGCCGUGGUGGAAACUUUGGUGGAAGAGGAGGCUAUGGUGGUGGAGGUGGUGGCAGCAGAGGUAGUUAUGGAGGAGGUGAUGGUGGAUAUAAUGGAUUUGGAGGUGAUGGUGGCAACUAUGGCGGUGGUCCUGGUUAUAGUAGUAGAGGGGGCUAUGGUGGUGGUGGACCAGGAUAUGGAAACCAAGGUGGUGGAUAUGGUGGAGGUGGAGGAUAUGAUGGUUACAAUGAAGGAGGAAAUUUUGGCGGUGGUAACUAUGGUGGUGGUGGGAACUAUAAUGAUUUUGGAAAUUAUAGUGGACAACAGCAAUCAAAUUAUGGACCCAUGAAAGGGGGCAGUUUUGGUGGAAGAAGCUCGGGCAGUCCCUAUGGUGGUGGUUAUGGAUCUGGUGGUGGAAGUGGUGGAUAUGGUAGCAGAAGGUUCUAAAAACAGCAGAAAAGGGCUACAGUUCUUAGCAGGAGAGAGAGCGAGGAGUUGUCAGGAAAGCUGCAGGUUACUUUGAGACAGUCGUCCCAAAUGCAUUAGAGGAACUGUAAAAAUCUGCCACAGAAGGAACGAUGAUCCAUAGUCAGAAAAGUUACUGCAGCUUAAACAGGAAACCCUUCUUGUUCAGGACUGUCAUAGCCACAGUUUGCAAAAAGUGCAGCUAUUGAUUAAUGCAAUGUAGUGUCAAUUAGAUGUACAUUCCUGAGGUCUUUUAUCUGUUGUAGCUUUGUCUUUUUCUUUUUCUUUUCAUUACAUCAGGUAUAUUGCCCUGUAAAUUGUGGUAGUGGUACCAGGAAUAAAAAAUUAAGGAAUUUUUAACUUUUCAAUAUUUGUGUAGUUCAGUUUUUCUACAUUUUAGUACAGAAACUUUAACAAAAUGCAGUUUCGAAGGUGUUUCCUUGUGAGUUAACAAGUAAAGAAGAUCAUUGUUAAUUACUAUUUUGUAUGAAUUUUGCUAAAGUUAACUGUAAAGAAACACCUGCUGACUUGCAGUUUAAGGGGAAUCUAUUCUCCCCAUUUCCAAACCAUGAUAUGAAUGGGCGCUGACAUGUGGAGAGAAUAGAUAAUUUGUGUGUUUGCAAUGUGUGUUUUAGAUAAAUAGGAUUGGGUAUUUAAAUUAGCAUUUGUGAAUUUAAUAGCAUUAAGAUUACCUUCAAAUGAAAAAAAAUCUCAAAAUUUCUAUUUGGUUUUUGUGCAUUUUCUUUUAAAAUGUAAUCAUAUGAUUUUAGUGUGUUAGACUUGCUGAGUCCUAGCUGUGUUUAGAACAUCUCUAUUCUACAUUUACCUUGGUCAAAUUUGAACUGCUGCCAUAGGUUUUGGGUGUAAAGAAUGUUUACUGCCCUCCAUUUAAAUUCUGAAAAGGGAUGGUGGAUGUUUUCCCUCUCCUACGUUAGAAACCAUUCUUAAAAACUUUUGAAAAUAUAGAACCAUUAAGCCUGCUAUAUCUGAGCAAAUUAGUGGGUACCUUUUUUUUCUUAUUUAAAGCACAAGAGGCCCAUAAAUCUUGAGUUACUUUAAAUUCUUUUUUUUGAUACAAGUUUUCAGAGCAAGAGAAUAAAAAUCAUGUGUUAUUAAACCCCUAACUGGCUGGCAUGCUUUCCUGUUUGUAUUCUAUACAUUUUGCUGGAUGAAACCAAGGAUAGUUCAGGUAUAAUUGUCCAAAAUAACCUAACUGCAGCAGAAAUGUAGCACAGUUGCUUAGUACAGGCUUCUCACUUCCUACAGACCUGAAUUCAAAUUUGGAUAGUCUGAGUUCUUAAAUUCCCAAAGAACACACUGUUAUUUCUUGUGUAUAUUUCAACAUAAAUCAUGUUGUUACCAAUUUGUUUGGAAGGCCCUGGUUGAGAAGAGUUUUAGUUAAUAAGGUCAUAUAUACAUAUAUUAAUAUAAACCAAUGUCUACUGUUUUGCUCCAGCUAGUGCUUACAGUUUCAUUCGAGCCCUGAGUAUGUGCCCUGCUGUUACUCUCUUUGGUAGUUGAACGUUGAAUUCAAGUCUUUUGUUUUAAGAAGUACUAAGCAAACAAGCAAUAAAAAGGGGAAUGGGGUGUGCUAGUGUUUGAAUAUGCUCUCUUGUUGCUCUAAUUCUGUGCCUCUGUGCAUUAAUAUUUGGAUGCAUGCAAUGCCAGCAUGGAAAUUGGUCUUCACACAUACUGCAGUUUUCCAGAAACAUUCACAAACCAAUAAAUGUAACAGACAUUCCAUUUGUUAAUGGGCAUAUAUGUGAAAAGCAGUGUAGAAAAUAGGCUAAUAUUAGAAAAUGGUUAAGUCCUAAAUAACUUCAAGUGUGGUUAUAUAAUGGACACUGUCAAUGUUCAUAACUUAAACCUGGGUACCUGGUCAAAAUAAUGCUUGGGAAACAUUAAAAUUGAGCUAAAUUGUCUCAAGUUCUUUUAUUCAUAUAAAUAAAGUUUAAAGGAAUGGGGGAGAUUAACAUUUCCUGUUUUAUGUUUGUGAAAUUGUUUGACACAACCUUGACAGUAUCCUUUAAUGGCAUGAGGUUAAUUGUACUGUUAACCAACUUUCUAUGUUCUGGAACUAGUAUUAUAGUGAAAACAUUUACAGUAAGUUGAUGUUUACAACCUAUAAGCAGGUGAAAUCUGUGUAUGUGACCUGUUUAUAAGUUGUAUUAGCUUAGCUCUUGUGAACAGUGUGGAAAAGUAAGCCAUGAGGAGAGCGAUUUAACCACCUUUAAAGGACCUAAGAUGUGCUUUUUAAGCACAGUGUGGAUCACAGAAACUCACUAAGACAGGACUUCAGCAGCCUUUUGUGUUUGGACAAGUCAGCAUAAAUAAAGAAUGACAAGGCAGCAGCAAGAGCUUCAACUACAGAGAAGUGAAGGCAUAAGAUACUAUGAUGAUAGUGAGCAACUUUCCAAAAGCUAGUUAAAUCUGCUUAUUACAACUGAAAUAUCGAAGAAAGUCUAGCAGGAAGGAGCUCUUCGCCUUUUGGAACAUCAAUGAGAGAUAGUUGCCACAGUCACUAGGUCUAGCAUUUAGACCUGCAAGGAAGGGCAAUAAGCAUUAGGUAAGGCUUGAAUUUGAAUUUUUUCACUAAUUAAAGAGUAAUUUUUUGUAAAGCAAGGUAAGAGUAAUCUUUUUGAUUUGCAGGUUGAAUGAGAACCCUACUUGCCUAAAUGAGGAAUGUCUUUCCUACCAUCUAAAAUACGAAGGUUUCUGGCUGGGUAAGGUUUGUAGUUGACAGUAAAACCUGAUGACACCAUUUGUUUCCCUGCAAGUCUACAUUACAUAUUUCACAACUUUGUCCCUCUCUAGUAGGCACAUUGGAAAAAUUCUUCAACUGAAAACUACCUUGGUACCAUGUCCUACACGUUUUAAACCUUAGUUUUAAAAAUUCCCCUGCGAAAUAGCCAUAAGUAUUCAUAUCAAGUCAGUUGUGACUCCUUGUGUAUACAAUUCAUUUUUUGUGUCUUCAGGGUAAACUCAAUUUUUGGUAAAGUGGUUUCAGCUUUUGUGAAAACCGUUUUGGUGUGUAAGCAUGACACACAACAGACUCAGUAAGCUGCCCAUCCUCAUACUAGGAAAACACCUUCAAAGGAACAUUAAAAGUUACCAGGGCCAGGCACAGUGGCUCACGCCUGUAAUCCCAGCACUUUGGGAGGCUGAGGCAGAUGGAUCCCAAGUCCAGGAAUUUGAGACGAGCCUGGGCAACAUAGUGAGAGCCUGUCAACAAAAAAUAGAAAAAUUAGUUGGGCUUGGUGAUACACAUCUGUAGUCCCAGCUAUUUGGGAGGCUGCCUUGAUAUCAGGCAGUCGAGGCUGCAGUGAGCUGACUGCCCCACUGUAUUCCAGCCUGGGUGACCCCAUCUCAAAGAAGAAAAGUUACCAGAUGUCAUGGGUAAAGGUUGGUCUUCAAGUGGCCUCAUAAGUUGUCUUGCAUUUAAAUUCAGGGAAUUCAUUGGACCAAUAGGUUACAUUUUCGUUCCUUUUUUGUUUUGGUUCAUCUGUUAAGCAGUGGGGGCCUAAUUACUGCUCCUUUGUAAAAACACAUUUUCCCAAAGAACACUGAAUUACCGUUCAAACUGGUUGUUGAUGGGUAAUAAGGGCUGUUUUUGCUGCCCCAAAAGGGCUUAACAAUUUAGUCGGAUAGUUUACUUAAAAAAAAAAAUCCUUUGGAGACAUACUGAAAAUGCAAACUAGUUUCUAAAUUAUCAAUUCCCUACAUGAAGAAGCAGUUUGCCAGAGUUUAGUCUCAGAAAAUGACUGGUUGGCUCUAUUUAAAUCAGAACCCAAUUUCUACGCGUGUUGAAUAAGGUAACAGCCUUUGAUGAAUUUCCUUCACAACAUGGUUUUAGUGAAGCAAACAUUUUUUUUUUAAGGGCAUUGUUCUUUCUAGUUUAUUUCUUUUUAUGAAAUAAAAUUAUUUUAUUUAAACAGUUCCAUUGUCGUUUCUGAAAACUACAGUAUUCUCAGAAGUUGUAGCAGCAGUAAAAAAAAAAAAGUUGUUAUAUAAGUGAUUGGGGCAGAUUUAACUGAUUUUGUUAAACCAAUUUGUAAGUUACUGCUUCUAAUAUUACACUUCUAAAAAGCUGAAUUUAUACUCAUGUCCUAAAGGAGAAUAUGUGGUAAUAAAGUAUAUUUGUUAAGUAACUAAUUGAAAUAGGCUUGGUUUUAAGAGUUCCAGUAUAUAAUAAUCACAAAUUGAAACCUGACAGUAUCUUGGGAGUUCCAGUAAUGUCACAAAUUAGUGAAUAAGCAUGCCAGUGUGCAAGGGUAAUGUAAGGAUUGUUAGCCUAUCUAAAUAUUCAAAAUUACUUUAAAACUUAAGUAUGUUUUCUGAUUUUUAAGAAUUCAGAAGUGUUCUGUAAUGGAUUCAGAUGUUUCAUUUGUAGUAUAAUGAAAUGUUUACAGAAAGAUAACUUUUUCAUUAAAAUAUUUUUAGAAAUGUGUGUGUUGUUUUGUCACUUCACAAUGUUCAUGUGACUUAAACACUAUAGGUGAAUAUUUUGACUUAUUUUACCAGUAAGUAAUAAAACAACAGGAAACUUGGA